CUCCCUCCCUCGGUCCCCGGGGCCGGCGGACCCGCGGGCAGGCACUGCCCGGGCUGGACGACGUCUGGCCGGCUCCCGGCGAAGGGCAGCGGAGGAGCGGCCCAGAGCGCGCAGCUAGGGCACUGGCGAAACCCCGGGACAGUCCCUCUCCGUGCGGGGGCGGCGCAGAGCAGUCCCAUCCCCGGGGUCCCGGGCGCGGCUGACUGCCGGCUGGUUCCCUGCGCGCAGUAGCUCCCCGAGCCGGGCUGCACCGGAGGCGGCGAGAUGGUCGCGCGCGUCGGCCUCCUGCUGCGCGCCCUGCAGCUGCUACUGUGGGGCCACCUGGACGCCCAGCCCGCGGAGCGCGGAGGCCAGGAGCUGCGCAAGGAGGCGGAGGAGGAAACUGAGGCAUGAAAAAUGCCUCACAGAAGAGGGUUAGGGACACCUCCAGGAGCAGAGGGAGUUUCAACCCCACCACCUCCUCACCCGGGAAGUUGGAUCUGCCUCCACUCCACAGAAUGUGAGAGCACCCAGCCCUGACAGCAUUAAGGAGCCCCUUCCUGCAUUCCUAGAGAAGUACGGAUACCUCAAUGAACAGGUCCCCAAAGCUCCCACCUCCACUCGAUUCAGCGAUGCCAUCAGAGCGUUUCAGUGGGUGUCCCAGCUACCUGUCAGCGGCGUGUUGGACCGCGCCACCCUGCGCCAGAUGACUCGUCCCCGCUGCGGGGUUACAGAUACCAACAGUUAUGCGGCCUGGGCUGAGAGGAUCAGUGACUUGUUUGCUAGACACCGGACCAAAAUGAGGCGUAAGAAACGCUUUGCAAAGCAAGGUAACAAAUGGUACAAGCAGCACCUCUCCUACCGCCUGGUGAACUGGCCUGAGCAUCUGCCGGAGCCGGCAGUUCGGGGCGCCGUGCGCGCCGCCUUCCAGUUGUGGAGCAACGUCUCAGCGCUGGAGUUCUGGGAGGCCCCAGCCACAGGCCCCGCUGACAUCCGGCUCACCUUCUUCCAAGGGGACCACAACGAUGGGCUGGGCAAUGCCUUUGAUGGCCCAGGGGGCGCCCUGGCGCACGCCUUCCUGCCCCGCCGCGGCGAAGCGCACUUCGACCAAGAUGAGCGCUGGUCCCUGAGCCGCCGCCGCGGGCGCAACCUGUUCGUGGUGCUGGCGCACGAGAUCGGUCACACGCUUGGCCUCACCCACUCGCCCGCGCCGCGCGCGCUCAUGGCGCCCUACUACAAGAGGCUGGGCCGCGACGCGCUGCUCAGCUGGGACGACGUGCUGGCCGUGCAGAGCCUGUAUGGGAAGCCCCUAGGGGGCUCAGUGGCCGUCCAGCUCCCAGGAAAGCUGUUCACUGACUUUGAGACCUGGGACUCCUACAGCCCCCAAGGAAGGCGCCCUGAAACGCAGGGCCCUAAAUACUGCCACUCUUCCUUCGAUGCCAUCACUGUAGACAGGCAACAGCAACUGUACAUUUUUAAAGGGAGCCAUUUCUGGGAGGUGGCAGCUGAUGGCAACGUCUCAGAGCCCCGUCCACUGCAGGAAAGAUGGGUCGGGCUGCCCCCCAACAUUGAGGCUGCGGCAGUGUCAUUGAAUGAUGGAGAUUUCUACUUCUUCAAAGGGGGUCGAUGCUGGAGGUUCCGGGGCCCCAAGCCAGUGUGGGGUCUCCCACAGCUGUGCCGGGCAGGGGGCCUGCCCCGCCAUCCUGACGCCGCCCUCUUCUUCCCUCCUCUGCGCCGCCUCAUCCUCUUCAAGGGUGCCCGCUACUACGUGCUGGCCCGAGGGGGACUGCAAGUGGAGCCCUACUACCCCCGAAGUCUGCAGGACUGGGGAGGCAUCCCUGAGGAGGUCAGCGGCGCCCUGCCGAGGCCCGAUGGCUCCAUCAUCUUCUUCCGAGAUGACCGCUACUGGCGCCUCGACCAGGCCAAACUGCAGGCAACCACCUCGGGCCGCUGGGCCACCGAGCUGCCCUGGAUGGGCUGCUGGCAUGCCAACUCGGGGAGCGCCCUGUUCUGAAGGCACCUCCUCACCUCAGAAACUGGUGGUGCUCUCAGGGCAAAAUCAUGUUCCCCACCCCCGGGGCAGAACCCCUCUUAGAAGCCUCUGAGUCCCUCUGCAGAAGACCGGGCAGCAAAGCCUCCAUCUGGAAGUCUGUCUGCCUUUGUUCCUUGAAGAAUGCAGCAUUGUCUUUGUCUGUCCCCACCACAUGGAGGUGGGGGUGGGAUCAAUCUUAGGAAAAGCAAAAAAGGGUCCCAGAUCCCUUGGCCCUUUCCUCCGAGGACUUCUAUCCUCCCCAGGCCUUUGUUUCUUCGGCUAAAGGUACAGUUCCUUUCAAGAGGUAACAGCACUGGGAUCCAAGCAGGGGGAUGAAAAACUCAGCAGAGAAAUUCGAGACCAUUUUGCAAGACUGUGCCCUUCUCCUCAGGACCCCCUGGCUCAGUUCUUGAAAAACGGUGUCAUAUUUAGUCAGAGGCCCCACCCCCAGGAAGCAUGGAUGGGGAUGAAGGCACAGGCGUCUCCAACCUCAGAGGCCCUUUGUGGGGUCAGGACACAGAGUGGGAGGGAGACUGAUGCAGGCCUACCAGUCCCUGGCUUUUUGUCUGGGGCUGGAAUAAAGAGGUGCCUUCAGCUGGUGGGCCGAGAGGCAGGAA